AUGAGGGGGCUGCGGGCUUGCAGUAGAGACCUGCGCUUAGCUGCUGGUGCGGGGCAGGCCUGGGGCAGCGCGGGGCGAGGAAGGCGGGGUCCGGCUCCACGCGGUCAAACGGGGACGCAGGGCGUGGGCAGUGGUGGCAGUGGAGCGGGAGUACGACCAGAGCCAUGUGCGGGGCAGCGACCGGCAGGAGGGAAAGCCCUGCGCGGGGAAGGGCAGGCCCAGGCCGCCCAGGGCUACGCGGCCGCGAACGGUUGGGGGACGGUCCUGGUCUCUGGCCUGGUCCCGCAAGAUCCCCGCGCUGCGCCGCCUCCCGGAGGAAGGCAGCUCCUCCUCCUGCGCCCACCUCGCUGGGUACCCAGUUGUUUCCCAAACUCACAAAGCGCAGACAUCUCCCAAGAGGACAGGAAGCCUGCAAAGAGGCGCCCCACACACUUUUAUCACCCAGACGAACACAAAGCCCAGCCCUCCCACGUCCGGGGUUCCCGGCGCCCGGGUUCCCCGCGCUCCGCCUCCCCCGGCGUCGGGCGCAGCUGGGCGUCAAGCUGGGCGGGGGUCCCUCGCCAGCCUCUGGCGCUCGACCUUCGCCCCACCUGGAAGGCGCCGGAUGCGAGACUCGCCCUUGGCUCGGCCCGCGGCCCCGGCCGGCGCCUCGCCCUUCACCUUCAAGUCCCCGAGGGAGCUCGGCAACUCGGCCCAAGGACAGGGGCCCAGCCUAGCCGUCACCGCCGGCAGCGCGCUCCGGGUCUGGCUCUGGUAGUCACUGGCGUAUCCCGCAUCCGGCCUGCUCACGGCGCUCCAGGCCUGCCCCGCGCGCCGAAACCCUCCGCCGGACGCGGAGGAAAAGAAGGUGGUGAGCGAGGCACGGAGAUGCUCCGACGGCUGCGCGGGUCUCCGAGGCCGAACCGCCACCCGCGUUCCGGGCCAGUCCCAGCCCACGGCGUGGCCAGCGCUGCCGCCGGUCCAGCGACACUGCGGGCGCCCCCGGGCCGCGGGGCCUCUUCUGAGACCAUGUGGCCCACAGAGAAUCUAAGCUCCCGCCGCCGGGCUCCACCUCAACGGCGGAGAACUCGGGCGCCGAGCAUCGCCCGAUCCCUACCCGGCAGCGGACGGCUACAGGGUUUGAUUUUCCCCUCCACAGGAAAGAACGUGCAGAGGCACAAAUCCCCUCCUCUUCCCUCAGAGGAAAGCCUGUCCCAGCGGUCCCGCUGAGAACUUCCGAAGCCUUGGCGCGGCAGGCAGGCCCCUGAGCCGGUGCACCGCGAAGUUGCAUUCUCACCUUCGAGUCACCGUGGCUUAGGCCGAGUAAACGAGCACUUCAUCUAGCGCCGGGCGGGCCCCGGCACCAAGCUAAGAGCUCAAAACUCCUCGAAGCGGGCGCGCGACGUCGCGGUCCGAGCUCUCCUCGCCGCACUCCCCCAUCAGACCUAAGAUCUUUUACCUUUUAAAUUAAAGUGAAUCCAGAUCCUUGUUAAUGCGGCCUAAUGUAGCAGCGGGAAGAGUGUAGGUCCCUGGCGAGGGGAGCGCGCUCCGGUGACCUCUAGCGCCUCAGACGCCCGCGCAGGAGGAACUCCCGCAGCCCGCCCGGGACCCGAGGGCAGGAGGGUGCGGGGAACGGGGCUGCCACUGCGCCUAAGCCUUUCCCCUUUUAUAGGCUUUAGGGAAACAAAUCCUCUUUUCCUAGUGGAUGUAAGAAGUGAGUGAAUUUAAAGUCACAGCCACGGCGGUAAGCGGCCCCAAUUGUCUGGGAUUCAUAAUGCUGUUAAUAUACACACGUAUAUGUAACAGCACUUUGCAGGUAUACAUACAUAUAUAUUAUAUGUAUUUUUUUUCAUAUGACGUUUGCAUCAAUAUUCUGCGUGCUGUCCCUCCCCCACCCCAACCCCAAUCUGUUUUUAAAAAUCCACCUCCGCAGAAGAGGAGAGGAGUGCUUCAGGGAAGGGUGGAGGCAUCCAUGUCCUCACCUUUCCCAGUGAGGAAUCGAGACUUCCCGCCUUCGCGAUGGAACUAGAAAAGGGUAUGUAGUCCUGGACUUUAAAAGACAAUUAACAGAAGUGGAAAUAAGGAUGUAACUAUAUUCCGAGGAAGAGCGGGCAGGAAAUUCUUAGCUGUCGUAGCAGAAAGUAAAUGUCUAAAACUCAUAAGCCUAAAAUUAGCCAUGCAGGUACAUUAAUUAAUUAACCACUAGACAAGCAGAAUUAUUAAUGUAGGUAAUGCCCAGUAGGGGGAAGAAAAAAGGAAUUGAUUCUGACCUGUGGCACUGGGGCUGGGGAGAGAUGGAAACUUCUGACAACUCUGUUUAUAUUACAAGCCCGUCUGCAAUGUUGUUUGAGUUGUUGUAAGCGUGUGCAUCAUUUACAUUUUUAAAAUUAUUUUUAAAUGAAUAAAACAAUAAUGUUUUCUAUA